CUGACAACACUAAUCAUCUUUUUUAUGGAGUGUUUCCUUGGUGCCAGGCAGUUCCUGCCCUCAAAGAGCCUCAAGAAUAUAGACUUCAUGAAAACAGGGACGUUGGUUAGUUCACUGCUGUUUCCCCACCACCCCAGAUAGUUCCUGGCACAUAUAGGUGCUCAACAAAUAGUUGAAUGAGUGAAUGAAAGCAUGUCUUGGAGGAAACAGAUGCUCACAAUACCAGGUGAUAAGAGCUGUACGUGAUAGGAAAUUGCAAAGCAAGUGACCAAUAGUGAGGCUCACCAAAUGCAAGCUUAGUCGGUGAAGGCUUCCCAGAGGAGGUGAUUCCAGAGUUCACCCAGGGAAGCAAAGGUCAAGGGGUAUUUAGGGUAGGGGAAAUAGUGCAAGUCCAGGCCUAGAGCUGAGGGAAAGCAAGGUGUACUGCCCACUCAGCUGUGUAUCCCUGAGGAGAGCCAGAAUUGUAGUCUGGGUAUGAACAGAUGACAGAGAGCAAGGUAGAGCAGGGGGAAAGGAUAUGAAGGAGCUUAGAACUCUCCCAGGAAUGAUCAGGAGUCCGGAAGAUUCUAAACAGUGGAAAGUCUGGUCUAAUUAGCAUAUUAGAAUUUGCCCUUUAGCUACAUGAUGGAGAAGGGAAUAGAGGCAGAGAUGCUCCUGAUGGAGACUAAGGGUUUGGACUUGCAGGGGAUAAACUUCAGGAGCUGCCGAGAAGGUCCAGUUAGAGGGGAUUUGCUGUCAAAUGAGAGCUGCUGUCAGGAAGACGUCCUUAUAUUGGAUAGAAUCCAGGAGUCCUGCCAAAGUGGCACCAAGUGGCUGGUGGAGACCCAGGUGAAGGCCAGGAGGCGGAAGAGAGGAGCACAGAAGGGCAGUGGAUCCCCAACUCACAGCCUGAGCCAGAAGAGCACCCGGCUGUCUGGAGCCGCCCCUGCCCACUCAGCCGCAGACCCCUGGGAGAAGGAGCAUCACCGCCUCUCUGUCCGGAUGGGCUCACAUGCCCACCCAUUACGGCGAUCAAGGCGGGAGGCUGCCUUCCGGAGCCCCUACUCCUCAACAGAGCCCCUCUGCUCUCCCAGCGAGUCUGACAGUGACCUAGAGCCUGUGGGGGCGGGAAUUCAGCAUCUCCAGAAGCUGUCCCAAGAGCUAGAUGAAGCCAUUAUGGCGGAAGAGAGAACUCUCCGUGGCUCGUCUGUGCCCUGCCUGCCUAUGGAAUUGGGAAAAGCAACCUGACUGCUAUGGAGUUCCUGGUCUGUCUGCUCAUGGCCCCAUCCUGGGGGCAGGGCCUCGGUUGUGGACCUCCCCUAACUUGGGGCUGUUUCCCCAUUCCACUUGUAUAAUGGCCAUGAUGGGCUCUAAGGCUGGGCCCUGCCAGCUCUAUGUGUUGAGGGGCCAUAUUCCUACCACAUUUCCGGGUCUGAUCUUGUGUAGCUCAGGCUGGGAGGGCCCUCUCAGAGCCCACCACACCCAGUGGCAUCAAUCCCUCCCCUUCUCUCUAGUGGUGACAUCGUCUCUCUCAUUCAUGACUGAGGAAGUGCCUGCAGGUAAUGCCCACCUCCCAAGAGUCUUUCUCACUGUCCUUCUCCUCCAUCUCAUGCAUGAGCAAGUUAAAGAAAAAGCCCACAGAGCUGAUGGGCACAGCAGAGUAGGUAGUACCUACUUGCCGCUUGAAGCCAGAGCUGCUAACCUCACUGACCCCGUCAUUAACAGCACGCUGGGGGCCCCAAGUAGCUACAGCCACCUUCCAGCACCCCCCACCCCGCAGUGAGCAGGGAAAGGCAUCCCUACUUCUCCUACCUUGAGCACAGUGAAAAAGGCAGCUCUGUCUUGAAGGAAACAAGCCCUGUCUGACCGCCAAGGCUUCAUACUCAAGGAUGUCUAUGCUUCCCCGUGAGCUUCCUGGAAAAAACCCCCGGGAGUCGUCAGUACCCCUGGGCCACUGCUAACAAGCACCUAACAAGGGGCCCAGAGCCCCCUGCUCCAGCCACAUCUGGACCCAUCAGUGACUGCCUGCCAUAGCCUGAGAGUGUCUUGGGGAGACCUUGCAGAGGGGGAGAAUUGUUCCUUCUGCUUUCCUAGGGGACUCUUGAGCUUAGAAACUCAUCGUACACUUGACCUUGAGCCUUCUAUUUGCCUCAUCUAUAACAUGAAGUGCUAGCAUCAGAUAUUUGAGAGCUCUUAGCUCUGUACCCGGGUGCCUGGUUUUUGGGGAGUCAUCCGCAGAGUCACUCACCCACUGUGUUUCUGGUGCCAAGGCUCUUGAGGGCCCCACUCUCAUCCCUCCUUUCCCUACCAGGGACUCGGAGGAAGGCAUAGGAGAUAUUUCCAGGCUUACGACCCUGGGCUCACGGGUACCUAUUUAUAUGCUCAGUGCAGAGCACUGUGGAUGUGCCAGGAGGGGUAGCCCUGUUCAAGAGCAAUUUCUGCCCUUUGUAAAUUAUUUAAGAAACCUGCUUUGUCAUUUUAUUAGAAAGAAACCAGCGUGUGACUUUCCUAGAUAACACUGCUUUCUCAUAAUAAAGACUAUUUGCAUUUGA